ACACGCGCGCCGCCCGGCCCCACUCGCGCAGCGCGGGCCUCCGCCGGCCGCAUUGUCCGCCCGCCCGCCUUGUCCCGCGUCGCCGCUCUUCGCGUGCCCGCGCGCCCCGGGCCCGGCCGCUGUGUCGCCCUGAGCGGAGCGCCGCCCGCGGGAUCCCCACGCGGAAAGGGGGCGCGCCCCGGCGGCGGCCUGGCCUCGGACGCCCCCGGCCGGGCUAGAAGCCGCCGCGGCAGCAGGUGUCACCUCCUUCAGCAGGACAGAGGCUAAGAGGAGUCCCUGUGUGGGCAGCUGGAGCCUUCAGAUUCUCUUCAGGGGAAGAGUCCACAUCCCACCUCAUCAUGUCCCGAAGAAGCCAGCGCCUCACGCGCUACUCCCAGGGUGACGAUGACGGCAGCAGCAGCAGCGGAGGGAGCUCGGUGGCUGGGAGUCAGAGCACCCUGUUUAAAGACAGUCCUCUCAGGACCUUGAAGAGGAAAUCCAGCAACAUGAAGCGCCUGUCCCCAGCGCCACAGCUGGGCCCGUCCUCUGAUGCACACACCUCCUACUACAGUGAGUCGCUGGUCCACGAGUCCUGGUUCCCACCCAGGAGCUCCCUGGAGGAACUGCAUGGUGACGCCAACUGGGGUGAGGACCUGCGGGUGCGGAGGAGGAGAGGCACGGGUGGCUCAGAGAGCAGCAGGGCCAGCGGGCUUGUGGGGCGCAAGGCCACCGAGGACUUCCUGGGCUCUUCCUCGGGCUACUCCUCUGAGGACGACUACGUGGAAGACAGUGAAGGAAGAGGCUCGAAAGUGACAGAGACUGAGCCAGUGUCCUCGUUCCCCGCAGGCUACUCGGAUGUGGACCAGCAGAGUUCCAGCUCGCGGCUCCGAAGCGCCGUCUCACGGGCGGGCUCCUUACUCUGGAUGGUGGCCACUUCGCCAGGCCGGCUCUUCAGACUUCUCUACUGGUGGGCUGGCACCACCUGGUACCGCCUGACCACAGCUGCCUCCCUCCUUGACGUCUUCGUUUUAACCAGGCGCUUCUCGUCCCUGAAGACGUUCCUCUGGUUCCUGCUGCCGCUGCUCUUGCUGACGUGCCUGACGUAUGGUGCUUGGUAUUUCUACCCCUAUGGGCUGCAGACAUUCCACCCUGCUUUGGUUUCCUGGUGGGCAGCGAAGGACAGCAGGAGGCCGGAUGAGGGCUGGGAAGCCAGAGACUCAUCGCCACAUUUCCAGGCUGAGCAGCGUGUUAUGUCCCGGGUACACUCUCUGGAGCGGCGUCUGGAAGCUCUUGCUGCUGAAUUUUCCUCCAACUGGCAGAAGGAGGCCAUGCGGCUGGAACGUCUGGAGCUGCGGCAAGGGGCUCCUGGCCAGGGAGGUGGUGGUGGCCUGAGCCACGAGGACACCCUGGCGCUGCUGGAGGGGCUAGUGAGCCGCCGUGAAGCUGCCCUGAAGGAGGAUUUCCGCAGGGAAACUGCUGCUCGCAUCCAGGAAGAACUGUCUGCCCUGAGAGCAGAGCAUCAGCAAGACUCAGAAGACCUCUUCAAGAAGAUCGUCCGGGCCUCCCAGGAGUCCGAGGCUCGCAUCCAGCAGCUGAAGUCAGAGUGGCAAAGCAUGACCCAGGAGUCCUUCCAGGAGAGCUCUGUGAAGGAGCUGAGGCGGCUGGAGGACCAGCUGGCCGGCCUGCAGCAGGAGCUGGCGGCUCUGGCACUGAAGCAGAGCUCGGUGGCGGAAGAAGUGGGCCUGCUGCCCCAGCAGAUCCAGGCCGUGCGGGACGACGUGGAAUCUCAGUUCCCGGCCUGGAUCAGUCAGUUCCUUGCCCGAGGUGGAGGGGGCCGCGUGGGGCUCCUUCAGAGAGAGGAGAUGCAAGCUCAGCUGCGAGAGCUGGAGAGCAAGAUCCUCACCCAUGUGGCAGAGAUGCAGGGCAAGUCGGCCAGGGAAGCCGCGGCCUCCCUGAGCCUGACGCUGCAGAAAGAAGGUGUGAUUGGAGUGACAGAGGAGCAGGUGCACCACAUCGUGAAGCAGGCCCUGCAGCGCUACAGUGAGGACCGCAUCGGGCUGGCAGACUACGCCCUGGAGUCAGGAGGGGCCAGCGUCAUCAGCACCCGAUGUUCUGAGACCUACGAGACCAAGACGGCCCUCCUCAGCCUCUUCGGCAUCCCCCUGUGGUACCACUCCCAGUCACCCCGAGUCAUCCUCCAGCCAGAUGUGCACCCAGGCAACUGCUGGGCCUUCCAGGGGCCACAAGGCUUCGCCGUGGUCCGCCUCUCUGCCCGCAUCCGCCCCACAGCCGUUACCUUAGAGCAUGUGCCCAAGGCCUUGUCACCCAACAGCACUAUCUCCAGUGCCCCCAAGGACUUCGCCAUCUUUGGGUUUGACGAAGACCUGCAGCAGGAGGGGACACUCCUUGGCAAGUUCACUUACGAUCAGGACGGCGAGCCUAUUCAGACGUUUCACUUUCAGGCCCCUACGAUGGCCACGUACCAGGUGGUGGAGCUGCGGAUCCUGACUAACUGGGGCCACCCCGAGUACACCUGCAUCUACCGCUUCAGAGUGCAUGGGGAGCCCGCCCACUAGCCCUGCUUACUGGUGCCUGCUGCCAGCCAUCUGGGAGUGGGUGAACAGCACCCCGCCGCUUCCCCCACACGCUUGCUCGGCGCUCUGACUUCUAGGAGCACAAGAGAGGAGCCUGUGGCCCCAUGCAGAUGAAAAGGACGGGCAGGGUCUCCUGAGCAGCAGGUGGCUCGAGGCGGUUAGCAGGCUCCAGCAGCUCCCUUCUUCCUUCCCUCUGUGCCCGUGGCGUCUGCUUCCCAUCCUGGGAGUGUGUAUAUAUGUAGCAUAUCAUGGGGGACUGGGAAGUUGGGAGAGGUAGGACCUGACUGGUCUUGGCUGGGGUCAGGGGCUGGUGCCUGGGAGCUGAUGAAGCAGGUGCCAGGGCUGUGGGAGGGGCAAGCUACGGCCUGGGCUAGGUGAGCUGCCUCUGCCCCUGGGCAAGGAAGCGAGGCCCUCUGGGAGGAGGGUGCUUAGCUCCAGAGCAGGAUGGGACUUCCCCAGGCAGGAAGCACUUGAUGGAGAGCUGCCCAGCUCUCCUACAAGGUUAGUGCCCUCCACCUAGGGAAGCAUGAACCACAGGGUCCCUGAGGGCCUUCGACAAAAGUGUGUAUUUGUCCCGGGGAGGGUAGCAGUGGGCCAUGGGGCUUCUUGUGCCCUAAAGGGGACUGGCUGCUGUGAUCUUCUAAGGGGCCCAGGGCCAACCCUGUAGGCUUCCCCUCUGCUGGGGACGGUAGUUGCUUUUCUCUCUCCUGAUGCUAGGUUGGGGCCCACCCUGCUCCCUGUUCCUGCUAGGGCCUGCCAGUGCCCCUGAGCUUGCUUUCCACAUUCUCCCAGGGUAUGGAGACCUAGACCUGUCUUUGGGGCCAUUAGCAUCUGGGGUUAUAGCAAGAAGAGUGGGGAGCAUGGAACUCCUGGGCUCUUGUGGGGACGUUCAGGGUAUCGGGGUGCGAGGUCUGUCUGCACCGGCCCCCACAUCUAACCAGGCCCUGAUGUAGGGGUCGUCCGCUCAGGCUGCCCCCUUGGGCUCUUGCAGCUCUUGUUCAGGUAGUCGCCCUUCUGGUUUGUUCUCUGUGGGGCAGUUGGUGGGGGCUGGGGGAAGAGGCUGGCAGAAGUUACCCUGGAUAGGGAAGGGGGAGGAGGGGACUUUUAGAGCCAGCAGGCCCCACUGUAUUAUGUAUAUAUUUUUCAAGGUCUGUUUUUCUAACUGAAAAGCUAAGGGCUUGAUUCCUAGCCCCGUUCUGUGGGGCACUGGGUGAUACUCAGUUUCUUGUUCCUGGCCGUGGAGAGGGGCCUGGGGCACUGGUUCCGGCUGUGUCUGGUGGUCUGGCUGCGGGGAAGGGGCAAGAAGGCGGGCAGGCCUUCACUGCAGCACUGAGCCUCAAAUCCGCUCUGGAGCAUGAGGCUGGAUGCAGUGGUGGUGAGGCCGCCCCGCUCCAUCCCGAGGCAGCCAGGGUUUGUUUUGCGCUCUCCUGUCACAAAUGCUGCACUAUUGGUUCUUAAGUUUUUUAUCUCCAGAUCCUAAUUUAUGCCUAUGCAAAAAAUAAAUGACGCCCAAGA